GCAGAGUUGCGACGCUCGGCGGCAUAGGGGGCGGCUCCACCGACACUACGCGGACGCCUCCUGCCGCAGGCAGGUUGAGCAGAGUGCCUGGGUGGGCUUCCCCCACGGCGGGGCGCGGAGGGAGGGUGGGGCUUCGGCUUGGCCUUUCAAGCCGGCAGGCGAGAAGCUUCCGACGGUUGAGGCGGAGCCGUUGUGGAAGCUGCCGAGGGGGAGGGGGUGCGGUUCUGCGGCAGUGGGCGGAGGGGAGGCGCCGAGGCUGGGCCAGGGCGUGGGCUGUGCAGAGUUCGCGGCGAGGGUGGCUCGCGCAGGCGCGAGGCUCCCCAUCAGCACCUGCCUGGCCAGCCUCGGCCUCGGGGAUGGGAAAUGGGCGCUCGGAGCCGCCCCCGCGCGUGGGCGACUCGGUCAAGGUGGCUGAGGCGCGGGGCGGUGCGCUUGGCGAGCGGGGAGCAGGCCUGGGGCUGCGCGCGUCGCCGGCCCGAGGAGGCUGAGGGGUGCGGGAGAAGCGGUGGCGACGGGAGCCCUGGGGACCGCUGCUCGCCUGUCUCCGGGACAUCUGAAGGGGGGUUGGCGCUGCGGCCUGGGGCGCAUCUCGGGUGUGUGUGUGCUUUGUUGGUUCGGGGGUGACCCUGGGAAAAGGGUCACCGUGCCGGCGGUGGGAGCAGGGACUUCGCCUUCGGCCUCGUUGUUGCCACUGCCGGUUCCACUUAGGGAAGAAGGGAGUGCGCGCAAAACCUUCCUCCUGCUCGGCGCCUUCAGUCCCUUCUCUCCCUCCCGCCGUCCCCACCUGCGGCCUCUCCUUGCGGUUGAGGCCGCCAGCCCCUCCGCGCAGCUGGGCCUGAUGCGUCCCGCGGCGGCUCAAUGCGCGACACGUGGCUCCACGUGCGGCCUUUUCUGGACCGGGCUCCAGGCUGGCCGAGCAUCUGCGAAUACGGCAGCGUGGUUUUUUUUUGUUGUUUUUUUUCCCGAGACGGAGUCUCGCUCUGUCACCCAGGCUGGAGUUUAGUGGUGCGAUCUCGCGUCACUGCAACCUCCAUCUUCCGGGUUCCAGCGAUUCUCCUGCUUCAGCCUCCGGAGUAACUGGGACUACUUGGCGCGCCACCACGCCCAGCUAAUUUUGUAUUUUUAGUAGAGACGGGUUUUCUCCAUGUUGGCCCGGCUGGUCUCGAACUCCUGACCUCAGGUGAUCCACCUGCCUCGGCUUCCCAAAGUGCUGGGAUUACAGGUGUGAGCCACCUCGCCCGGCCUACAUUUUUUAGUAAUGAUGGGAGGAGGAGGACGCCUUCCCUCCCCUUCAUUCACCUUUAAUGUCUUUUUGGACACCUUAGCUAUGUUAGUUACCAGGGCAGAGGGGACUUUGAAUUAUCUACUGCUGCUUGCAUUCAUUCAGCAGUUUUUCCUUUGGGGGAAAAUCUUUGCCUCCCCCAUCUGCCAAAUUGUUUUCUUUGUUGUUGUUUUUAUCCGUAACGCUUUUAUCUGCCUGCAGAUACACAAUCAUCAUCUUACUAGUUCUCUGUGUUGCUCGCUAACCAGUCCCCCAGUUCAGUAGACUGGAGCCCAGAGCCUGCUUACUUGUCAGGUGUUUAUUUUGUCUUGCUUUUUUUUUUUUUUUAAAUGAAGUCAAAAUGCCAAUAAGACCAGAUCUCCAGGUAUGUAGUCCUAGACCAAAACAGUUGGAAAAAUGCAUUGAUGAUGCUUUAAGAAAAAAUGAUUUCAAACCUUUGAAAACACUUUUGCAAAUUGAUAUUUGUGAAGAUGUGAAGAUUAAAUGCAGCAAACAGUUUUUCCACAAGGUGGACAACCUUAUAUGCAGGGAACUUAAUAAAGAGGAUAUCCACAAUGUUUCAGCCAUUUUGGUUUCUGUUGGAAGAUGUGGCAAAAAUAUCAGUGUAUUGGGGCAAGCUGGACUUCUAACGAUGAUAAAACAAGGACUAAUACAAAAGAUGGUUGCCUGGUUUGAAAAAUCCAAGGACAUUAUUCAGAGUCAAGGAAAUUCAAAAGAUGAAGCUGUUCUAAAUAUGAUAGAAGACUUAGUUGAUCUUCUGCUGGUCAUACAUGAUGUCAGUGAUGAAGGUAAAAAACAAGUAGUGGAAAGUUUCGUACCUCGCAUUUGUUCCCUGGUUAUUGACUCAAGAGUGAAUAUUUGUAUUCAGCAAGAGAUUAUAAAAAAAAUGAAUGCUAUGCUUGACAAAAUGCCUCAAGAUGCCCGGAAAAUACUCUCUAACCAAGAAAUGUUAAUUCUCAUGAGUAGUAUGGGAGAAAGGAUUUUAGAUGCUGGAGAUUAUGACUUACAGGUAGGCAUUGUAGAAGCUUUGUGUAGAAUGACCACAGAAAAACAAAGACAAGAACUGGCACAUCAGUGGUUUUCAAUGGAUUUUAUUGCUAAGGCAUUUAAAAGAAUUAAGGACUCUGAAUUUGAAACAGAUUGCAGGAUAUUUCUCAACCUUGUAAAUGGCAUGCUUGGAGACAAAAGAAGGGUCUUUACAUUUCCUUGUUUAUCAGCAUUUCUUGAUAAAUAUGAGCUGCAAAUACCAUCAGAUGAAAAACUUGAGGAAUUUUGGAUUGAUUUUAAUCUUGGGAGUCAGACUCUCUCAUUCUACAUUGCUGGAGAUAAUGAUGAUCAUCAAUGGGAAGCAGUUACUGUGCCAGAGGAAAAAGUACAAAUAUACAGCAUUGAAGUGAGAGAAUCAAAGAAGCUACUGACAAUAAUUCUGAAAAAUACAGUAAAAAUUAGCAAAAGAGAAGGGAAAGAAUUGCUUUUGUAUUUUGACGCAUCACUAGAAAUCACUAAUGUAACUCAAAAAAUUUUUGGUGCAACUAAACAUAGGGAAUCUAUCAGAAAACAAGGUAUUUCAGUUGCCAAAACGUCGCUGCAUAUACUUUUUGACGCAAGUGGAUCACAGAUUCUAGUGCCAGAAAGUCAAAUCUCACCAGUCGGAGAAGAGCUCGUUAGUUUAAAGGAAAAAUCAAAGUCCCCAAAGGAAUUUGCUAAACCUUCAAAAUAUAUCAAAAACAGUGACAAAGGGAAUAGAAAUAAUAGUCAGCUUGAGAAAACUACUCCUAGCAAAAGAAAAAUGUCUGAAGCAUCAAUGAUUGUUUCUGGUGCAGAUAGAUACACUAUGAGAAGUCCAGUGCUUUUCAGCAACACAUCAAUACCACCACGAAGAAGAAGAAUUAAACCACCACUGCAAAUGACGAGCUCUGCAGAGAAACCUAGUGUUUCUCAAACAUCAGAAAAUAGAGUGGAUAAUGCUGCAUCACUGAAAUCUAGAUCAUCAGAAGGAAGACAUAGAAGAGAUAAUAUAGACAAACAUAUCAAAACUGCUAAGUGUGUAGAAAACACAGAAAAUAAGAAUGUUGAAUUCCCAAACCAAAAUUUUAGUGAACUCCAGGAUGUUAUACCAGAUUCACAGGCAGCGGAAAAAAGAGAUCAUACUAUAUUACCUGGUGUUUUAGACAACAUCUGUGGAAAUAAAAUACACAGCAAAUGGGCAUGUUGGACACCUGUAACAAACAUUGAACUAUGUAAUAACCAAAGAGCAAGUACUUCGUCAGGAGACACAUUGAAUCAAGAUAUUGUUAUAAAUAAAAAACUUACUAAACAAAAAUCAUCCUCUUCAAUAUCUGAUCAUAAUUCUGAAGGAACAGGAAAAGUGAAAUAUAAGAAAGAACAAACCGACCAUAUCAAAAUAGAUAAAGCAGAAGUAGAAGUUUGCAAGAAACACAAUCAGCAACAAAAUCAUCCUAAAUAUUCAGGGCAGAAAAAUACUGAAAAUGCCAAGCAGAGUGAUUGGCCUGUUGAAUCUGAAACUACUUUUAAAUCGGUUCUCCUAAAUAAGACAAUUGAAGAAUCGCUGAUAUAUAGGAAGAAAUACAUAUUGUCAAAAGAUGUGAAUACUGCUACUUGCGAUAAAAAUCCAUCUGCUAGCAAAAAUGUGCAAAGUCAUAGAAAAGCAGAGAAAGAAUUGACUUCUGAGCUUAAUUCCUGGGAUUCGAAACAAAAAAAAAUGAGAGAAAAGUCAAAAGGGAAAGAAUUUACCAAUGUAGCAGAAUCCUUGAUAAGCCAAAUCAAUAAAAGAUACAAAACAAAAGAUGACAUCAAGUCUACAAGAAAAUUAAAGGAGUCUUUGAUUAACAGUGGUUUUUCAAACAAACCUGUUGUACAACUCAGUAAGGAAAAAGUUCAGAAAAAAAGCUACAGAAAACUGAAGACUACCUUUGUUAAUGUUACUUCUGAAUGCCCAGUGAAUGAUGUUUACAAUUUUAAUUUGAAUGGAGCUGAUGACCCUAUCAUAAAACUUGGAAUCCAAGAGUUUCAAGCUACAGCUAAAGAAGCUUGUGCGGAUAGGUCAAUUAGAUUGGUAGGUCCAAGGAAUCAUGAUGAACUUAAAUCUUCUGUCAAAACAAAAGAUAAAAAAAUUAUAACAAAUCAUCAAAAGAAAAAUCUGUUUAGUGAUACUGAAACAGAGUACAGAUGUGAUGACAGCAAGACUGAUAUUAGCUGGCUAAGAGAACCGAAAUCAAAACCACAGCUAAUAGACUAUAGCAGAAAUAAAAAUGUGAAGAAUCAUAAAAGUGGAAAAUCAAGAUCAUCCUUGGAAAAGGGACAGCCAAGCUCUAAAAUGACACCCAGUAAAAAUAUCACAAAAAAGAUGGACAAGACAAUUCCGGAAGGAAGAAUCAGACUUCCACGAAAAGCAACCAAAACAAAAAAAAACUAUAAAGAUCUCUCAAAUUCAGAAUCAGAGUGUGAACAAGAAUUUUCACAUUCAUUUAAAGAGAACAUACCAGUAAAGGAGGAGAAUAUCCAUUCCAGAAUGAAAACGGUAAAGCUACCAAAGAAACAACAGAAAGUCUUCUGUGCUGAAACAGAAAAGGAACUAUCAAAACAAUGGAAAAACUCAUCUCUACUAAAAGAUGCUAUACGAGAUAAUUGCCUUGACUUAUCUCCCAGAUCUUUAUCUGGCAGUCCAUCAUCUAUAGAAGUAACGAGAUGUAUAGAGAAAAUAACAGAAAAGGAUUUUACUCAGGAUUAUGACUGCAUAACAAAAUCUAUAUCACCUUAUCCAAAAACUUCAUCACUUGAAUCCUUAAAUAGUAACAGUGGAGUUGGAGGUACAAUAAAGUCACCCAAAAACAAUGAGAAAAACUUCCUGUGUGCAAGUGAAAGUUGUUCACCAAUUCCACGACCACUGUUUUUGCCCAGACAUACUCCAACUAAGAGUAAUACUAUUGUAAAUAGAAAAAAAAUAAGUUCUCUGGUACUUACACAAGAAACACAAAACAGUAACAGCUAUUCAGAUGUAAGCAGUUAUAGUUCAGAAGAACGGUUUAUGGAAAUUGAAUCUCCACAUAUCAAUGAAAAUUAUAUACAAAGCAAAAGAGAGGAAAGUCAUUUAGCAUCUUCAUUAUCCAAGUCUAGUGAAGGAAGAGAGAAAACGUGGUUUGACAUGCCCUGUGAUGCUACUCAUGUAUCAGGCCCCACCCAACAUCUUAGUCGCAAAAGAAUAUAUAUAGAAGAUAAUCUAAGUAAUUCCAAUGAAGUAGAAAUGGAAGAGAAAGGAGAAAGGAGAGCAAACUUGCUUCCCAAAAAACUGUGUAAAAUUGAAGAUGCAGAUCAUCAUAUCCACAAAAUGUCUGAAAGUGUAUCUUCAUUAUCAACAAAUGACUUUUCUAUUCCUUGGGAGACCUGGCAAAAUGAAUUUGCAGGGAUAGAGAUGACUUAUGAGACUUACGAGAGGCUCAAUUCAGAAUUUAAGAGAAGGAAUAAUAUCCGACAUAAAAUGUUGAGUUAUUUUACUACGCAGUCUUGGAAAACAGCUCAGCAACAUCUGAGAACAAUGAAUCAUCAAAGUCAGGACUCUAGGAUUAAAAAACUUGAUAAAUUCCAAUUCAUUAUCAUAGAGGAGCUGGAGAAUUUUGAAAAAGAUUCACAGUCUUUAAAAGAUUUGGAAAAGGAAUUUGUGGACUUUUGGGAAAAGAUAUUUCAGAAGUUCAGUGCAUAUCAAAAAAGCGAACAACAGAGGCUUCAUCUUUUGAAAACUUCAUUGGCUAAAAGUGUCUUCUGUAAUACUGAUAGUGAAGAAACUGUUUUUACAUCCGAGAUGUGUUUGAUGAAAGAAGAUAUGAAAGUGCUGCAAGACAGGCUUCUUAAGGACAUGCUAGAAGAGGAGCUUCUUAAUGUACGCAGAGAACUGAUGUCAGUAUUCAUGUCUCAUGAAAGAAAUGCUAAUGUGUGAAAUCUAGUUUUUAUCACCAUACUUUAUCUAAUUAUUAUUCUCUGUAUAUAACUGAGGAAAUAAGAAUAGUCCUACAAAGAGAAAAAUAUACAUGUCACCGAAGCAAGUGUACCCUUUAUAGGAACCCUCAAAUUAAAAAAAAAUGUCUUUUAAUGGAUGAGAGGGAACCACUAUAACAUGAGUCCAAGCCCAGAAGACUUCUGUCUAUACAAUAUUUUUUUUUAAUUUUGGAGAUAAAAGCUUUAAGAAACUUUUUGAGUUAAUUAUACUCAUAAAAUGAGUUUCUUUAAUAAAUUAAAUUUUAUUGUGUAAAAUGUAUUAUUACAUAAAAUGUGUUUUUGAAUCAAUGCAGUUUGGGGAUGAAUAUAAUUAAAAUAUGUUUAAUAACUUAGAAUUCAACUAAUAAAAAUUUAGCCACACUUACAAGGGGGAGGAAGUCCCUAGUUUAAAAUGUAUAACUGAGUGGUAGAUCAGUACUUUCAGCACACUGUUGGAAACAUUUAUUCAGAUAUGGCUCUAAUGUAUUAGGAAGCACUAAAUGGCCUAAAAAAGCUACUACAUUGCCUAAAUAUGUUAAUUCAAUAUAGAAGUCCUAUUUCAUAACCAGGCUGUUUGACAAAUACUUUUAAUCUAGUAGUCAUUGUAAUAUCUUGCUAGAUUAAUUUAUAAAAAUGAGUAUACAUUUGAUUUGCUUUUAAUGAAGUUGAAAUAAAUGCUUAUGUCACUUGAAUAAAUAUAAA